AGGCGCUGCUGCUGGCGCCAGACGGCACCGGCCGCUGGUAGAGCGCGUGCCGCGAGAUGCGGCCUCAGGACAGCACCGGGGUCGCGGAGCUCCAGGAGCCCGGGCUGCCGCUAACGGACGAUGCACCCCCGGGCGCCACUGAGGAGCCGGCGGCCGCCGAGGCAGCUGGGGCGCCAGACCGCGGUAGGUGCUGGCUCUGCCUUUCCUCGCCGUGUUGCUCCCGCACCGAGCCGGAAGCCAAGAAGAAAGCACCCUGUCCUGGACUUGGCUUGUUUUACACAUUAUUGUCUGCCUUCCUUUUCUCAGUGGGCUCUUUAUUUGUUAAAAAAGUGCAAGACGUCCAUGCUGUAGAGAUUAGUGCGUUUCGAUGUGUGUUCCAAAUGCUAGUUGUUAUCCCUUGCUUAAUAUACAGAAAAACUGGGUUUAUAGGCCCAAAAGGUCAACGAAUUUUCCUCAUUCUCAGAGGAGUCCUUGGUUCUACCGCCAUGAUGCUUAUAUACUAUGCUUACCAGACAAUGUCCCUCGCUGAUGCCACAGUUAUCACGUUUAGCAGUCCAGUGUUUACGUCCAUAUUUGCUUGGAUAUGUCUCAAGGAAAAAUAUAGCCCUUGGGAUGCUCUUUUCACCGUGUUCACAAUCACUGGAGUGAUCCUUAUCGUGAGACCACCAUUUUUGUUUGGUUCCGACACUUCGGGGAUGGAAGAAAGCUAUUCAGGCCACCUUAAGGGAACAUUCGCAGCAAUUGGAAGUGCCGUAUUUGCUGCAUCGACUCUAGUUAUCCUAAGAAAAAUGGGAAAAUCUGUGGACUACUUUCUGAGCAUUUGGUAUUAUGUAGUACUUGGCCUCGUUGAAAGUGUCAUCAUCCUCUCUGUAUUAGGAGAGUGGAGUCUGCCUUACUGUGGGUUGGACAGGCUAUUUCUCAUAUUCAUUGGGCUCUUUGGUUUGGGGGGUCAGAUAUUUAUCACAAAAGCACUUCAAAUAGAAAAAGCAGGGCCAGUAGCAAUAAUGAAGACAAUGGAUGUGGUCUUUGCUUUUAUCUUUCAGAUUAUUUUCUUUAAUAAUGUGCCAACGUGGUGGACAGUGGGUGGUGCUCUCUGCGUAGUAGCCAGUAAUGUUGGAGCGGCCAUUCGUAAAUGGUACCAAAGUUCCAAAUGAAGCAUCAUUGCUGAAAUACAUAUUUUUUUCAAGUACACCAUCACCUAAUUCACAUACAGCAUACGCACACAUCUGGAAAAUCUGCAUUUUCUUCAUUGGUUGUAUUUAAUAAAUUGCCUAAAGUACCAUUUUUGAAUAUAGUAUGUCUUUAGUUAAGAAUAGCUAGUCUGUUUGGUGUAACAAUUUUUUGGUAGCUUUGGUUUUGGUUUUGGUUUUUUUUGUUGUUGUUGUUGGGGUCAAGUUGGUGAGAGGAGAGCUCAUUGUUUGAAGAAAAACCAAAACAUUUUAUGGCUAGUAAUAUUUAUGUAAUUUUUAAAAUGUAUUUUUGGUACUGAUGGGAUAUGGGUGGGGAGGCUAUUUUAGAUAUUCUUUUAGCAGUGUAGAGCCUAAGAAACUUGGUUCUACUACCAUGAUCUUUAUAAACUAUGCCUUCCAGACAAUUGAUAAUGCUGCUAUAAUUAGUAUUAUGUUGAUAAUUCAUUUGCAACCUUAUUCUAUUUAGGAGGAUGAAGUUGAAGCUUAGAAUAGGUGCCUGCUUAAUGGUGUUAAUAAUACAAAUGAAUUGGCCUUAUUUUCAAGGAUUUUAUAAAUGAUUAUCAUACUUGUAACUCAUAUUUGUGCCUUUUCAUUUUAAUGCUGGAAUUUUUAUUAUGUCACCUCUAAAACACUUAAAUUGCCAAAUUUGGCUAGUAGUUUUGUUUCAGUGGCAUUAGCAACUGCAGCUAGCAUACUAUAAUUUUAAUUGUCCUCACUUUUUUUUGAAACUGCACUAAAUUUUUCUUAACAUUCCAAGAUUUCAGAUCUCUAAAUCACAAAGAGAAAUCUUGGCAUGACCAGUGUGCACGUUUCCAUCCUGAAGUGUUUUCUCUUCACUAGAAAUGUGAUUUUCUAUAAAUUCCCCUUGAAUUUAUAGUGUGAUGCCAAAUAAAAUUUUCUCAGGAUCUUAUUAGGUUGAACCAUAUGUAAUUGCCAAGAUUUUACUAUUUUAACUUAGAAAAACCAUCGUUUCAUAUGAUUCACCCUAAUAGAUACCUCCAUUAUUCUCUAAAUGAAAUAGAAGACUUUGGAGUAUAUGUUUUUAAAGUAAUUUUUUAAAAUAUGGUAAUGUAUUAAACUUAUUUUUAUAGUUAUGAAAUUAUGUGUAAUAAUGCUUUAUGUUAUACAUUAAAUGUAAAGACUUGUGAAUCCAUGUUUGAUUGACUUUCAUAGUUUCCUGCAUUGAAAUAAAAUCACUAUGAAUUCUAGUUUAUCAGCAUGAUGUUAAAUGUCAGUGCCAUACCAUGAUGCAGCACCAUGACACUAACGCCAUGAAUUCAAACAGCACGUUUUACACCUGGAACUUCAUCAGACCAAUACUUUGCAGUUAGAGAGAAUUUAAUAUCUAGAAAAGCUUGGGAGGUUAGUCAGGACUUAGGGAGUAUACAUAAAUGGUUACUUGUUGUAAUGAGCCCUUUAUUGGUGAGGUUGCAAUAGCUUCCAGCUCUUACUGUGUCAGAUGAAGCAUCUGUCAUUAUCUUAAGCCUGCAGAGUUGAAAGGUUAUAGGCUCUUUCCUACCCUCUCAUCAUAAUUUUUCCAAAGCAAAGAGGAACUUGGCUUCUGGGGUUCGUGCCUUAGUGAGAAAGAAUCUUUUCCAAUAGUUCCAAUGGGGGAAUUUUUGGCUUGCUGAUUUUAUCAAUUGCCUUGACACCUGACAAACCCUAAAUGAAGUCUAUGUAGGUGAGUCAUCUCUGUUCCACCUGAUUUACAGUAUUGGAAUUUAGACUUGCAAAAACAUCAUUCUGCAAAUAUCUUAGAUAAUUACAGAAUCAGGAGCAUUUGAGAACUCUAGAGGUCUCAGAAAUCAUCACAUAGGGGCCAUGCUUCGUAGAUAGGGAUGAUAGAGAGGAGACCUGCCCAAGUUGAAUUUCCAUGGCCUUCCUCCCUUCCUUAGUUCCAUGAUAAAGUAUGGACAGUAAACCACUACUUGAGCUACCUAAGGUGAAUUAACUCUCAGGGAACCCUCUUCCAGUUCUUUACCUUGCACAGUGAAAGAAUCAGUGGCACCUAGAAAGUUAAAUCCCUUUAGGCCCAUACACUAGAGACAUGUUUUGUUUGAACAAUGUAGUUUAAGUACUUGAAUGUCACACUAUAUAACUGAGGUUAGAGAAAAUGUUUCUUCUAGCCCUUACAGGGUGUGAUUCUUAAACACAAUGUCCAAGGUGUAUACAAGGAUAUGUAUUGUAACAACUAUGGGUAUGUAUAUUUUGCAGAGCGUAGUUUCUAUAUCUUGAAAAGGAAAAUAUUUUCAUAAAUUGUUUUUAUAAGUACUAAUAAAAUAAUAUGAAAGAAAGCUA